CUCUUUCCCUGCUGAUUCCAGGAGCCUAUCAACCCAGAUAAAGCGGGACCUCCUCUCUGGUAGAGGUGCAGGGGGCAGUACUCAACAUGAUCACAGAGGGAGCGCAGGCCCCUCGAUUGUUGCUGCCGCCGCUGCUCCUGCUGCUCACCCUGCCAGCCACAGGCUCAGACCCCGUGCUCUGCUUCACCCAGUAUGAAGAAUCCUCCGGCAAGUGCAAGGGCCUCCUGGGGGGUGGUGUCAGCGUGGAAGACUGCUGUCUCAACACUGCCUUUGCCUACCAGAAACGUAGUGGUGGGCUCUGUCAGCCUUGCAGGUCCCCACGAUGGUCCCUGUGGUCCACAUGGGCCCCCUGUUCGGUGACGUGCUCUGAGGGCUCCCAGCUGCGGUACCGGCGCUGUGUGGGCUGGAAUGGGCAGUGCUCUGGAAAGGUGGCACCUGGGACCCUGGAGUGGCAGCUCCAGGCCUGUGAGGACCAGCAGUGCUGUCCUGAGAUGGGCGGCUGGUCUGGCUGGGGGCCCUGGGAGCCUUGCUCUGUCACCUGCUCCAAAGGGACCCGGACCCGCAGGCGAGCCUGUAAUCACCCUGCUCCCAAGUGUGGGGGCCACUGCCCAGGACAGGCACAGGAAUCAGAGGCCUGUGACACCCAGCAGGUCUGCCCCACACACGGGGCCUGGGCCACCUGGGGCCCCUGGACCCCCUGCUCAGCCUCCUGCCACGGUGGACCCCACGAACCUAAGGAGACACGAAGCCGCAAGUGUUCUGCACCUGAGCCCUCCCAGAAACCUCCUGGGAAGCCCUGCCCGGGGCUAGCCUACGAGCAGCGGAGGUGCACCGGCCUGCCACCCUGCCCAGUGGCUGGGGGCUGGGGGCCUUGGGGCCCUGUGAGCCCCUGCCCUGUGACCUGUGGCCUGGGCCAGACCAUGGAACAACGGACGUGCAAUCACCCUGUGCCCCAGCAUGGGGGCCCCUUCUGUGCUGGCGAUGCCACCCGGACCCACAUCUGCAACACAGCUGUGCCCUGCCCUGUGGAUGGGGAGUGGGACUCGUGGGGGGAGUGGAGCCCCUGUAUCCGACGGAACAUGAAGUCCAUCAGCUGUCAAGAAAUCCCGGGCCAGCAGUCACGCGGGAGGACCUGCAGGGGCCGCAAGUUUGACGGACAUCGAUGUGCCGGGCAACAGCAGGAUAUCCGGCACUGCUACAGCAUCCAGCACUGCCCCUUGAAAGGAUCAUGGUCAGAGUGGAGUACCUGGGGGCUGUGCAUGCCCCCCUGUGGACCUAAUCCUACCCGUGCCCGCCAGCGCCUCUGCACACCCUUGCUCCCCAAGUACCCGCCCACCGUUUCCAUGGUCGAAGGUCAGGGCGAGAAGAACGUGACCUUCUGGGGGAGACCGCUGCCACGGUGUGAGGAGCUACAAGGGCAGAAGCUGGUGGUGGAGGAGAAACGACCAUGUCUACACGUGCCUGCUUGCAAAGACCCUGAGGAAGAGGAACUCUAACACUUCUCUCCUCCACUCUGAGCCCCCUGACCUUCCAAACCUCAAUAAACUAGCCUCUUCGAGUUCGUCUACGAUUCCUUAAAGGAGGAAAAACAACCUAUCCCCUUCCCCAAAAGUAGGGUGAUAGCAUCUCAUAGGGCAAACAGCACAGCACGGGCCAAGACACAGCAGCCUGUUGCGGAAAACAGUAUUUUCCACUGUGGUCGCAGGUUGGCAGGAGUGAAAGCGAGUGUGCAGUCCCAGCCUCUCCCCGCCGCUGCCAUAACCCCAAUGUCUGGGCCCUGCGCAGCCCCCUUAGAGCCUCAGGGCCGCCCGGCACGUUCCUCUGCAGAGCUCCGCGUUACGGGUUUCCUGAUUGGCUACUUGUCCUGGCAGGCACUUCUUGAUUGGCCGGCGUGCUUGUUCGUUGUCUCCCCGUCUCCUGGACCUCCCUAGAUUCCCACCAGCCGGAACCCUGGAGGAGCCUCUGCCGGCCGACUCCGACUCCGCGUCAGUCGAGGAUGAACGGCAGAGGCGUGGCCGAGGCUGGCACCCUGCCGCCCGAGCACCUGCACCCACCCACUCCCGACAGCCCAGCUCCAAUGCCACAAUUACCAGCGACAAAUAGCUCGGCGAGGCGGGGGGCGGGCCGAGGAAGUGCCUGUGUUGCGCUCUGAGCUGAGGAGGGGCAAAGAAGCUAGAGUCAGUAUCCGCCCGGAGGAGCCCCCAAGACAAAUCCAGACACUUUCCUCUGGUAAUUUGUUCAUUCAUUCAACACUUAUUAGCGCCUGCUGUAUGCUAAAGCUGAGUCUGAGCAUCUAGGGUGGAGGAGGGCUGGUAGAAAGAGGACAUCUGAGUGAGGGAACAGACUCAGAAGGUAUUCCUUUCGUGUGAACAUCUAUUCAACACUUAACGCCUACUGUAUACUAACAAUAGUGCUGGACAUCACGGAGAAUAGAGAAGAAGAGGAAUCAGAGCGUUACGUGUCUCCGCAGUAAAGGGAACAAAGCCAGA